AGUCGCUCCCAGUCCGCUGCGAGGAAAGCGCACCCGCAGUGUCUCUUCGCCGGGACCCCCGCCGAGCCGCCCUCGCCGCCGCCGAGCCCCGAGAGCAGCUGGGCUCCGCUUAGGCGGAAUCAGCGAGCGCCGCGCCCGGGCACUGCCGGCCCGAGGAGGCACCGCCCGCAAGGACACCACUCCGUCCCGUCUCGUCCGCAACUCCGGCCCUCGUCGAGCUCGACGCGAGCCAGGAUCCCGGACGUCUCUCCGCGUGCGGCGCAGCAGCAGCCAGACCAGUCCCUGCGACCCCACCUCGGAGGCAACUCCAUUUCGGACCUGGGACUUCUGACGCGGAUCCUCAGCUACUUCUCACCUCGGGGCUGUGCCCUCCUCCUCCGCUCAGGACGGGGGUGCCAAGAUGCCCCGCUGCAGCGCAGGGCCCCGGGCCGCCCCCGACGUGUGACCCUAGCCUGGUCCCCCUGCUCGGCCGUCCGCCCUCCCCUUGGAGACCCCCGGCCCGGCUUCCGGGGGAGGAGGAAGGAGACGACGAGGCCGAGGGGGGGAUGUCCGGCUCCAAAAGCGUGAGCCCCCCGGGCUACGCGGCGCAGAAGACUGCGGCGCCGGCGCCCCGGGGAGGCCCCGAACACCGCUCUGCGUGGGGCGAGGCCGAUUCCCGCGCGAAUGGCUACCCCCAUGCCCCCGGGGGCUCUGCCCGCGGCUCCACCAAGAAACCCGGGGGGGCGGUGACCCCGCAGCAGCAGCAGCGCCUGGCCAGCCGCUGGCGCAGCGACGACGACGACGAUCCUCCGCUGAGCGGUGACGACCCCCUGGCCGGGGGCUUCGGCUUCAGCUUCCGCUCCAAGUCCGCCUGGCAGGAGCGCGGCGGCGACGACUGCGGUCGCGGCAGCCGCCGGCAGCGGCGGGGCGCGGCCAGCGGGGGCAGCACCCGGGCGCCCCCUGCGGGCGGCGGCGGCGGCUCGGCGGCGGCGGCUGCCUCGGCGGGCGGGACGGAGGUGCGCCCUCGCUCGGUGGAGGUGGGUCUGGAGGAGCGGCGGGGCAAGGGGCGCGCGGCCGACGAGCUGGAGGCCGGCGCCGUCGAGGGCGGCGAGGGGUCCGGGGAUGGCGGCAGCUCGGCGGACUCGGGCUCGGGCGCGGGGCCCGGCGCGGUGCUGUCCCUGGGCGCCUGCUGCCUGGCGUUGCUGCAGAUAUUCCGCUCCAAGAAGUUCCCGUCGGACAAACUGGAGCGGCUGUACCAGCGCUACUUCUUCCGCCUGAACCAGAGCAGCCUCACCAUGCUCAUGGCCGUGCUGGUGCUCGUGUGCCUGGUCAUGUUGGCCUUCCACGCGGCGCGGCCCCCGCUCCAGCUGCCCUACCUGGCCGUGCUGGCGGCCGCCGUCGGCGUGAUCCUCAUCAUGGCUGUGCUUUGCAACCGCGCCGCCUUCCACCAGGACCACAUGGGCCUGGCCUGCUAUGCGCUCAUCGCCGUGGUGCUGGCCGUCCAGGUGGUGGGCCUGCUGCUGCCGCAGCCACGCAGCGCCUCUGAGGGCAUCUGGUGGACCGUGUUCUUCAUCUACACCAUCUACACGCUGCUGCCCGUGCGCAUGCGGGCCGCAGUGCUCAGCGGGGUGCUCCUGUCCGCCCUCCACCUGGCCAUCGCCCUGCGCACCAACGCCCAGGACCAGUUCCUGCUGAAGCAGCUUGUCUCCAAUGUUCUCAUUUUCUCCUGCACCAACAUCGUGGGUGUCUGCACCCACUAUCCGGCUGAGGUCUCCCAGAGACAGGCUUUCCAGGAGACCCGAGAGUGCAUCCAGGCGCGGCUCCACUCGCAGCGGGAGAACCAGCAGCAGGAACGGCUCCUGCUGUCUGUCCUUCCCCGUCAUGUUGCCAUGGAGAUGAAAGCAGACAUCAACGCCAAGCAGGAGGAUAUGAUGUUCCAUAAGAUUUACAUCCAGAAACAUGACAACGUGAGCAUCCUGUUUGCUGACAUCGAGGGCUUCACCAGCCUGGCGUCCCAGUGCACUGCACAGGAACUGGUCAUGACCCUCAACGAGCUCUUCGCCCGCUUUGACAAGCUGGCCGCAGAGAAUCACUGUUUACGUAUUAAGAUCCUUGGGGAUUGUUAUUACUGCGUCUCGGGGCUGCCUGAAGCAAGGGCUGACCACGCCCACUGCUGUGUGGAGAUGGGCAUGGACAUGAUCGAGGCCAUCUCGUUGGUCCGGGAGGUGACAGGGGUGAACGUGAACAUGCGUGUGGGAAUUCACAGCGGGCGAGUACACUGCGGUGUCCUUGGUCUCAGGAAGUGGCAGUUCGACGUCUGGUCUAACGAUGUCACGCUAGCCAACCACAUGGAGGCUGGCGGCAAGGCAGGACGCAUCCACAUCACCAAGGCUACACUCAACUACCUGAAUGGGGACUACGAGGUGGAGCCAGGCUGUGGGGGCGAGCGCAACGCCUACCUCAAGGAGCACAGUAUCGAGACCUUCCUCAUCCUGCGCUGCACCCAGAAGCGGAAAGAAGAGAAGGCCAUGAUCGCCAAGAUGAACCGCCAGAGAACCAACUCCAUCGGGCACAACCCACCACACUGGGGGGCUGAGCGCCCCUUCUACAACCACCUGGGUGGCAACCAGGUGUCCAAGGAGAUGAAGCGGAUGGGCUUUGAAGACCCCAAGGACAAGAACGCCCAGGAGAGUGCGAACCCUGAGGAUGAAGUGGAUGAGUUUCUGGGCCGUGCCAUUGACGCCAGGAGCAUUGAUAGGCUUCGGUCUGAGCACGUCCGCAAGUUCCUCCUGACCUUCAGGGAGCCUGACUUAGAGAAGAAGUACUCCAAGCAGGUAGACGACCGAUUUGGUGCCUAUGUGGCGUGUGCCUCGCUCGUCUUCCUCUUCAUCUGCUUUGUCCAGAUCACCAUCGUGCCCCACUCCAUAUUCAUGCUCAGCUUCUACCUGACCUGUUCCCUGCUGCUGACCUUGGUGGUGUUUGUGUCUGUGAUCUACUCCUGCGUAAAGCUCUUCCCCUCCCCACUGCAGACCCUCUCCAGGAAGAUCGUGCGGUCCAAGAUGAACAGCACCCUGGUUGGGGUGUUCACCAUCACCCUGGUGUUCCUGGCGGCUUUUGUCAACAUGUUCACGUGCAACUCCAGGGACCUGCUGGGCUGCUUGGCACAGGAGCACAACAUCAGCGCGAGCCAGGUCAACGCGUGUCACGUGGCGGAGUCGGCCGUCAACUACAGCCUGGGCGAUGAGCAGGGCUUCUGUGGCAGCCCCUGGCCCAACUGCAACUUCCCCGAGUACUUCACCUACAGCGUGCUGCUCAGCCUGCUGGCCUGCUCCGUGUUCCUGCAGAUCAGCUGCAUCGGGAAGCUGGUGCUCAUGCUGGCCAUCGAGCUCAUCUACGUGCUCAUCGUGGAGGUGCCAGGUGUCACGCUCUUCGACAACGCCGACCUGCUGGUCACCGCCAACGCCAUAGACUUCUUCAACAACGGGACCUCCCAGUGGAGCCUGUGUGAGAACCUCAGACACAGGAGAAUGGAAGCUGGUACCUACUUUCCCUCUGGAGUCAAGGAACAAAGCCCUGAGCAUGCAACCAAGGUGGCAUUGAAGGUGGUGACGCCCAUCAUCAUCUCAGUCUUUGUGCUGGCCCUGUACCUGCACGCCCAGCAGGUGGAGUCCACUGCCCGCCUCGACUUCCUCUGGAAACUGCAGGCCACAGAGGAGAAAGAGGAGAUGGAGGAGCUGCAGGCCUACAACCGGCGGCUGCUGCACAACAUCCUGCCCAAGGACGUGGCCGCUCACUUCCUGGCCCGCGAGCGGCGCAAUGAUGAGCUCUACUAUCAGUCCUGUGAGUGUGUGGCGGUCAUGUUCGCCUCCAUCGCCAACUUCUCCGAGUUCUACGUUGAGCUGGAGGCCAACAACGAGGGUGUCGAGUGCCUGCGGCUACUCAAUGAGAUCAUCGCUGACUUUGAUGAGAUCAUCAGCGAGGAUCGGUUCCGGCAGCUGGAGAAGAUCAAGACCAUCGGCAGCACCUACAUGGCUGCCUCCGGCCUCAACGACUCUACCUACGACAAGGUGGGCAAGACCCACAUCAAGGCACUGGCCGACUUUGCCAUGAAGCUGAUGGACCAGAUGAAGUACAUCAAUGAGCACUCCUUCAACAACUUCCAGAUGAAGAUCGGGCUCAACAUCGGCCCCGUGGUGGCCGGGGUGAUAGGGGCACGAAAGCCUCAGUACGACAUCUGGGGCAAUACCGUGAACGUGGCCAGCCGCAUGGACAGCACCGGUGUACCCGACCGCAUCCAGGUCACCACAGACAUGUACCAGGUGCUGGCUGCCAACACGUACCAGCUGGAGUGCCGGGGCGUGGUCAAGGUCAAGGGCAAAGGCGAGAUGAUGACCUACUUCCUCAAUGGAGGGCCCCCGCUCAGUUAGCAGCUGUUGGCCAAUGGUGCCAGGCAGCCUGGCCUCCAGAGGCAUGGAAGCAGCUUCUCUGUGUGCCGGGGGUGGCGGGGAAGCCAUGCUCCAGCCCGCAGGGCUGCGCUGCUGAGAUUUUCCACUUGGACUCCAGAGCAGCUUCUGCCUUUGCUGGUGGGCAGCGGCCUCUGUCCCAGGCCCCGGGGUGCCAGCGUCCUGCGAGCACCCAGCUGACCAAAGAUGUUUCCCUCUGUAGAAGACUCUGCUAGACUGGGUCUGAAGCUUGAGUUUUCUAACAGGUGCUGCUGCACAGGUGGAAAGGAGCCGUGGGAAUGUGUGUGUGGCACGGCCCAGACAAGGGCAGGGCUGAGGGGCCUCCGACUCAGCUGGGGGUAGACGGGCUCGAAUGUGGCCUGGGAGAGCCUAGGGGGCCCCAGGGGUCUGCUUUUCUAUGUGAGCCUUUAAACUUCAGACAGGCCACCACCCUGCACCUGCAGGGGCUUUGGCACAGGAGUGCUGGCUUUGGAGGGACUGUGGCCUUCAUCGUGGUCCUCUGCCCACACCUCCACGCACACAGACAGUGCCCUAGGAGGGAAACAGAACUAAUUACGAGGGGGAGGCAAGAGGACGCCAAGCAAGGAGUGGUGAUUCUGAGAAAAAUAUUUAUUAAAUAAAACAAAACAAGUUCUCCGUGCCCUUCUUUAGACUAUGCUAGUUGUAUGCGUGUAAGAGACACACAAGCAAACGAGGACGCCACUCGGGGGGAGGGCGGGGAUCCCCACUUGUCUUUUUUGUAUUUUUUAUUUUGUAUUAUUGAAAGCCUUGGAGAUCUCACAGAUAGAUAUGCCAAAUUCUAUAUUUUGUAAAUUCUCUAUAUUAGAAAACAGCUGUGCACAGCAGGGCGGGUGUGCUCAUUUGUACUGUGUGUAUGUCGGUGUAUGUACUGGUGUAUAUGUGUGUGUGUUCAUGCUGUGGAACUGGUCUCACACAGGAUGUGUUUCCCUCAUUUCAGAUUUGGCAGUUUUGGGUUUUCCAAGGUACCACCAGAGCAGUGGGUGUGUGCUUUUGGGGUACCAUAUGCUCAGAUUAAGUAGGAGGAUGCAUGGACACACUGCCCCAUCUUUUCUGACACACGCACACGUAUGUACACACAUGCACACACCCUCCUUCCCCUAAGCAAAACGCAGAUGGAAUAAGAAAACAAAAAGCUGCUUUCCCAUCCCAGGCCGAGCUGGAACCAAGGGAAGCAAUCUCAUCCUGCGACAGGCAGUGUGGUGCCCUCCACACCCUGAGAUUUCAGACGUUUGCGGCUUACAGAGGCAGCGCCCACAGAUUCCAGAGUGCUUACAGAAGGCCAGGUGCUUUGCAGGCUGGGACGAGGAAGCCAAGCCUCCCUGGCCUACUCAGUUGGCCAAGGUGCAGGUGGCUCUUCCUGGAGAUGUUCACUCAGACUGGGGGAUGCAAUGUGCAGCCUUCAGGUUUGCGGAAAGGGAGUGGCCUUGACCUCCACCGGCAAACCAGGCAGAGGAAUGGGUAGAGCCCAGCUUUAGAGUCCACAGGGAAAGCUAGCAGGAAUUUUGUUUUAGUGGGAGGGGGCAGUUAAACAUACCAAGAAAAAAAUACUAUUUUUAUAACCUAUGAGGAAGACAUUUGGAAAAUGAUACUCUAGCACAGAAUUCAGUGGAAUCCUUAGGGCCCAUGCCCAAAUCUUUCCAUUGCUUCUCAGGUUAGAAUGAUCUUCACCUCCAACAUGAGCUUGGAGGUGAUGAGGCAGUGGCUCUGUGCCAGCUGCCACAAUGUGACUUUGAUGUCCACCUGUACCACCUCUCACUGGGCUCUAGCACCACCCUCCCCUCCCCGCACACCAACUGAACACAGCUCUGAGAAGCAAAGUGUGUGGACCCAAAACUGCCAAGCCUGAGUCUGUCCCGUGCUUCUGCUGCUCCAUCCUUUGAGUUCUGCAUUGCCAUCCUGACGUCGGCCACAGGAGGCCUGCUUUCUUCCAGCUGUUGUUCUCAAGUUCCCUGCCCCUCCACAUCGCCCGCCAGUGGUGUUGGGUUUUCGUUCUGCUUCCAACCUGAGUAAAGUGUGUGUGCUGAGUUCAUCCCAUGUUCUCCCAUGGUCAUGGCUUCCCGGCCCCAUGGGGACCCCUCUCCCAUCCCAGCAGUGACUGGUGACAGUGUGCAGGUGCAGUGCUAGCUCUUCGUUCCCUCUAAAGGGUGUGCACUCUUUUUAUUCCUACUCUUGCAAAAACAGAUACGAUUAUGAUUUCCCAUGGAAAUUGAAAAGUCUAUUUAAAUAAUUUAACUAUUAAACACUUUCACUGGUAA